ACUAGAGUUUUGCUCCUGGGACGGGACGUCCGAGAGACCAAGAAAUUCUCGAGUUCUCUUCAGAGACCAACUGGGGAUCAACAAUUCAAUUUAAUUCUGACACCCAAGCUUUUGGUUCCAGAGGGCCAUAGUCUUCAUAUACUUCAGCACUCCAUGAAGGCUUUCUUGGUACUGUUCAAAGCUGUAGAAGCAUGGCACCAGCAUCUGUUUGACUUCUUAUGAGGCCUCAGGAAGCUUAUAAUUAUGGCAGAAGGUGAAGGGGAAGCAGGCAUGUCACAUGGCAAGAGAGGGAGCAAGAGAGAUGCCAGGCUCUGUUAAACAACUAACUCUCAUGUGAACUAACAGAGUGAGAAAUCACUCAUUACUUCAAGAACAGCACCAAGACAUUCACAAGGAAUCUGCCUCCGUGACCAAAACACCUCCCACCAAGCUCCAUCUGCAACAUUGGGGAUCACAUUUCAACAUGAGACUGGGAGGGGAUGCACAUCCAAACCAUAUCAGGGCCAGAGGAUCUACUACCACAGAACCAUUCUAGAUGUGAGUUCCUAGUGUGAAAGGACUGGGAGUUAACAGAAGAGCCACAGUGAGCAUGUCAGUGAAAAAACCAGUGAAUCGCCUUCCAAACCAGGAGAAAAGAAAGGAUCAGAUGAGAAAAAAGCAGCAAGCCUCGGCAGCAGUCAAUCCUCCAGAACCUAUGCUGGUGGAACAGCCUCGGCCACCAAGGUGUCAGCUUCCUCUGGUGCAACCAGCAAGUCUUCCAGUAUGAAUCCCACAGAAACCAAGGCCAUUCCAGUCAGCCAACAGAUGGAAGGACCACAUCUUCCUAACAAGAAAAAACACAAAAAACAGGCUGUAAAAACAGAACCUGAGAAGAAGUCACAGUCAACCAAGCUGUCUGUGGUUCAUGAGAAAAAAUCCCAAGAAGGAAAGCCAAAAGAACACACAGAGCCAAAAAGCCUACCCAAGCAGGCAUCAGAUACAGGAAGUAACGAUGCUCACAAUAAAAAAGCAGUUUCCAGAUCAGCUGAACAGCAGCCAUCAGAGAAAUCAACAGAACCAAAGACUAAACCACAAGACAUGAUUUCUGCUGGUGGAGAGAGUGUUGCUGGUAUCACUGCAAUAUCUGGCAAGCCGGGUGACAAGAAAAAAGAAAAGAAAUCAUUAACCCCAGCUGUGCCAGUUGAAUCUAAACCGGAUAAACCAUCGGGAAAGUCAGGCAUGGAUGCUGCUUUGGAUGACUUAAUAGAUACUUUAGGAGGACCUGAAGAAACUGAAGAAGAAAAUACAACGUAUACUGGACCAGAAGUUUCAGAUCCAAUGAGUUCCACCUACAUAGAGGAAUUGGGUAAAAGAGAAGUCACAAUUCCUCCAAAAUAUAGGGAACUAUUGGCUAAACCCAUAGGGCCAGAUGAUGCUAUAGACGCCUUGUCAUCUGACUUCACCUGUGGGUCGCCUACAGCUGCUGGAAAGAAAACUGAAAAAGAGGAAUCUACAGAAGUUUUAAAAGCUCAGUCAGCAGGGACAGUCAGAAGUGCUGCUCCACCCCAAGAGAAGAAAAGAAAGGUGGAGAAGGAUACAAUGAGUGAUCAAGCACUCGAGGCUCUGUCGGCUUCACUGGGCACCCGGCAAGCAGAACCUGAGCUCGACCUCCGCUCAAUUAAGGAAGUCGAUGAGGCAAAAGCUAAAGAAGAAAAACUAGAGAAGUGUGGUGAGGAUGAUGAAACAAUCCCAUCUGAGUACAGAUUAAAACCAGCCACGGAUAAAGAUGGAAAACCACUAUUGCCAGAGCCUGAAGAAAAACCCAAGCCUCGGAGUGAAUCAGAACUCAUUGAUGAACUUUCAGAAGAUUUUGACCGGUCUGAAUGUAAAGAGAAACCAUCUAAGCCAACUGAAAAGACAGAAGAAUCUAAGGCCGCUGCUCCAGCUCCUGUGUCGGAGGCUGUGUGUCGGACCUCCAUGUGUAGUAUACAGUCAGCACCCCCUGAGCCGGCUACCUUGAAGGGCACAGUGCCAGAUGAUGCUGUAGAAGCCUUGGCUGAUAGCCUGGGGAAAAAGGAAGCAGAUCCAGAAGAUGGAAAACCUGUGAUGGAUAAAGUCAAGGAGAAGGCCAAAGAAGAAGACCGUGAAAAGCUUGGUGAAAAAGAAGAAACAAUUCCUCCUGAUUAUAGAUUAGAAGAGGUCAAGGAUAAAGAUGGAAAGCCACUCCUGCCAAAAGAGUCUAAGGAACAGCUUCCACCCAUGAGUGAAGACUUCCUUCUGGAUGCUUUGUCUGAGGACUUCUCUGGUCCACAAAAUGCUUCAUCUCUUAAAUUUGAAGAUGCUAAACUUGCUGCUGCCAUCUCUGAAGUGGUUUCCCAAACCCCAGCUUCAACGACCCAAGCUGGAGCCCCACCCCGUGAUACCUCGCAGAGUGACAAAGACCUCGAUGAUGCCUUGGAUAAACUCUCUGACAGUCUAGGACAAAGGCAGCCUGACCCAGAUGAGAACAAACCAAUGGAAGAUAAAGUAAAGGAAAAAGCUAAAGCUGAACAUAGAGACAAGCUUGGAGAAAGAGAUGACACUAUCCCACCUGAAUACAGACAUCUCCUGGAUGAUAAUGGACAGGACAAACCAGUGAAGCCACCUACAAAGAAAUCAGAGGAUUCAAAGAAACCUGCAGAUGACCAAGACCCCAUUGAUGCUCUCUCAGGAGAUCUGGACAGCUGUCCCUCCACUACAGAAACCUCACAGAACACAGCAAAGGAUAAGUGCAAGAAGGCUGCUUCCAGCUCCAAAGCACCUAAGAAUGGAGGUAAAGCGAAGGAUUCAGCAAAGACAACAGAGGAAACUUCCAAGCCAAAAGAUGACUAAAGAAAUACAAGUUAAGGUAUCUGGUAUCUGCAUGUAAAAUCUUCAGCUGGUGGAUGGUGACUUUUGAAGAACAAAAGGCUUUGGCAACAGAAAACAAUUGUUCUGGGUGAUUUCUAGAAUGGUUUUUGUUGAGUCUCUGAACAUCCUAAAUAUUGGUUUGUUAUUCUUUUCCAGAAAGAAAAUGAAUUUGACUGGUUCACCUGUGUACUGAGUAUUGAUAAACUUUGAAUUUUUUUAAUUGCCUUCAAUUGGGAGAGAAAGCUUUAUAUUUGUAAGAAAUAUAUUUGAUAAAGUUUCUUAAAGCAACACCAAAAAAACAAAAGAAAAGCUAAGUGAAUUUUUGCACAUUCUACACACAGUGCCUGUAAAUCUCAUUUGUAUUUUCAGUUUGCCCUUAAUUUUUUUUGUUAGUGUUUAGAAAACAAUGUUUUAAACAUUCUUCAGUGUUCUGAUUUCUUAUUACCCCCUUUCCUCUUGGGCUUUUGAACUGUAUUUGAUGUUGCUUUGGGAUAAUGUUUAUAAGUCAAACAUAAGAUAUUGUACAUUGGGCACAUAUCUCCUCUUGGGCUGCUAAUAAUAAAUUAAUAACAGGUAACCUGGACAAACCAGGAAGCACCAAACCCCUUUUCAGUUUGAACUCUUCUUUGCCAGGUGUGAGGACUUCUGCAUCUUACAGUCAGCACAGAACACACUGAGACUUGAAUCAAGUCAGCAACAGAGCAAAAUAAAGGUUAGAUAAGUCCUUGUGUAGCAAAUUUCGAGCAUAAGAAAUAAAAUCUAAUUAAUUCUUAGGGUACUCAUCUGACUUGAACUCUGUUGGUUUACUGUGUUAGUAAACUGUGCUUUCUAUUAUCUAUACAUAAAACCUGAGCAGCAACUGUGUCUUUAGAGCUAUUGCCACAUUAGCCUUUGCACUGUAUAGCGUCUGGCUUUAUGGAACUUAAGUUUACCAAAUAUAAAAAGAAACUUCUGCUUUUAAAAAAAUUAUAUAUAUAUAUUAAAUUUGAAACCUGCAUUUCUCCCACAGCAAUGUAAGAAGUAGGCUCUGAUGUCCUACCACUUUGAAUGGUUUUCUAAUAUCUUAAUGAAUAGUUCCUGAACAUUGCACUGAUAUCAUCGAUUAGAAUUUUGAUAUUUAAUUUCAUCUUUAUUUCCUGGUAGAGAAUGCAGGAAAAGAUGUCAGGUACAUAACAUAAAACAGAUUGGGAAUUUAUUGUUUCCAAAGGGCAUGGCCUUCCUUAGCAUCAGUUUGAAGCUUUUGUUAUGACUUAGCUGACUUGUGGCAGCGGGGCAAGCAAAAACAAUAACACUGCUUAUAAAUGGCACCACAUCUUGUUAACCUCCCCCCCAAAUACUCUCUGAAAGUCAUGCACAUACCUAUGGGAUUUUACACACCACCAGCUUAAAAUGCUAUGUCUCUAUCCAUCAGAAAUAGUCAUUAUUCUAUUUUUAAGGCAGCAACAAGAAAAGAAAAAACACUUUUCCUGAGGGAUUUCUAACCAUGUAUCUAAUCCUCCCAUUUGGGCAGUAUAGGUGUUUGCUUUUUUGUUUUCUUUUUUUAAGAAAAACCUUGAAACCUUUGACACUGACAGAUGUGUUUGCAAGGAUACGGCUUCAGUAUUACUAAUUUCCAUGUGUAUCUGGAAGUAUUUUUAAAUGGCAUACCAAAAUCCAGAAGUUUAAAGAUGCCUAUAAAAGUAAACAACAUUUAUUUAAAAAGAACUCUGAAUAUGCCUUCUUUUUUAAUUAGAAAUAUCUUCGAGACUUGGGUGUUUGUUAAUAACUAAUAACUGGAGUAAGCUACAGGAUCUAAAGCAGCCCUUUUUACAGUCUAGUUAGGAGAGAGAAAAUAAUUGCAAAUAUCCACUUAGAGGCAAAGAACAAUUUUUUAUUAUCAAAAAGGUUUCUGCACAUUGUUGUGGCAAUAUUGUAUCUGUUUAGAAAAUGGGCUUUUCCAAAAGCAAACAAAGAUAGGUUCCUCAGGUGACCAAAACUGAAAAUCAAUAUUUCCAUGUUUCAUUAAUCAAGGCAUAAAAUACAAUUAAAGCAAAAUAUUUUACAUUAAAA